AGCCCAUCCAGGCAGCACGGCUGGCUGAGCAGAGACAAGGUAAGCUCUGGAGAGGCCAGGCAGAGUGGAGGGGGGUGCAAUUUCUUAAGUCAUGGGAAUUAAGGCCAAUUGAGGCAGGGAUUUCACCUCCAAAUAGUGGUUUGAAACCACUGAAAUGGAAAUUGCUAGGAAAACAGUGGGCCUGAGUCGCAGAUCAGGAAGCACCGGGAAGAUGCAGGCCUGCAUGGUGCCGGGGCUGGCCCUCUGCCUCCUACUGGGGCCUCUUGCAGGGGCCAAGCCUGUGCAGGAGGAAGGAGACCCUUACGCGGAGCUGCCGGCCAUGCCCUACUGGCCUUUCUCCACCUCUGACUUCUGGAACUAUGUGCAGCACUUCCAGGCCCUGGGGGCCUACCCCCAGAUCGAGGACAUGGCCCGAACCUUCUUUGCCCACUUCCCCCUGGGGAGCACGCUGGGCUUCCACGUUCCCUAUCAGGAGGACUGAAUGGUGUCCAGCCUGGUGCCCGCCCACCCCGCCAGGCUGCACUCGGUCGGGCCUCCACAGGCAUGGAGUCCCCGCAAAAACCUGGCCCCUGCAGGAGUCAGGCCUGGUCUCACGCUCAAUAAACUCCGGACUGAAGAUGCACAA